GUAUUUCGGGGCCCUAGGCGCGCGAGCGGUCAGCAUCCGGAAUCUGGCCCCUGCAGGCGUGGGGUUCCACGUGGGAGGUGAGACUGGCCGGGCUUCCCCAGCCGCUGGCAGAGGCGUUCAGGGGUCAGGAAAUGGGUGUGCCGCGGGUAAGGCGCUGGGCCGCCGAGCUGCGGAAGCCGGGAGGGCGGCGAUGGUAGGGCACGCGACCAGCGGAGGCGCGGCCCGCGGCGGCACGUGUGUCCCGGCGCCGCAUUUCCGAGCUGCUGCGCCCCCGGGGCCGGGCUGCGGCCACACCGAAGCCUGUGGGGCCCUGCAGCUGAGCGGCCGCGCCUCCGAUGGCCCCUCCUCCCUCCUGGCCGAGCUCUGGCCUGGGCCGGCUGGGGGCUUCGUGGUUGGCCACGCCGGCCUUUUCCUCGCCUGUGACGGGCGUUAUUGCAGGGGGGUUUUCGGUGGACGUUAGGCGACGGACGGGGGCUCCUGUAAGAGACUGAGGUUUCUGUCCGCAGCACUGCCUUCGCUGAAAAGAGCUUGCAUCUGAGCCCCCGCACCGCAGGAACGAGCCAGGCUCCUGAGAAUGAGGUCGGGGAAGGCGUCUUGGGCAACCGAAAUCCAUCCCGAGAAGCUUCUCCUCUUAACUAGAACUUUAGGACAGAGAUCGGGAAAGUCAGAGGAAAUGGGCACGGCUUCGAGCUGCCGGCGGCUGCGGAAUUUACCUAGCCUCUUGGUUUUGGGGGGAAAACUUGGCUUGUUUAAUCGAAAGCCCUGUGGAGAGAGAUGAAGGUGGUGACAGAAAAUGCUUCACCUCUCACCUGAUGGAGGGAGUGUGGGUGGAAGUGACUGAAGAAGCGUCAGAGGCAGGAGCGGAGUAACUUUUUCCCCGCAGUCUUGCUGGACUUGAUUUUCAUGGCUUUUUCUCUUUCCCUAACUCUGCCUUUCCAGGAAUCCAUCCCCUCUGGGAGUAAGAAAUGACCAGGGUCCGGGUGAGUUGGCGUUCCAUUUCUCCUAAAAUGCCAUCUCCCUGAAAUGUCCCUGUGCCAUGUGUUGUUUUCUUUAUUGUCAGGCCCCCAGUACGGUAUUUUAUAGCUAUGGAUGUAGGGACAUUAAGAUACUAAGGACAUGUAGCUAGCAGAUGAUGUCACCAGGGUCUGCACAGAGAGUUUUCACUGGCCCAUCCUGCCUCCAAGAAUUUAUUCCACUCCUCAGAGCAGUGGGCUGUGCCCUCCUGGGGAGCCUCUCAAAGCCUGCCUUUUCCUGCCAGACAUUUCACUCACAUUGAAAGUCAUUCCAAGCUAUUCCAUACUCAUCCCAGUGCUAAGUGGUCUCAGCAAAACAGAUAGAAUGAUAAACCACGGUGCUUUUCUUCAAGGAGCUUACCAUCUUGAUGAACAUAUUAUAUUACCUGUACACAAAAAAAUGCAUAUUAAUAGUGAUAAUUUAUUAACUAUGAGUCAAAAACGAGGAAAUUCGUUAAAUGGCAGCACAGUGGUUACAAAAUCACUCUAGAAAUGCUUUUCAACUAGGCUAUGCAUCAGAACUCUCUGUGGUGUUUUUUAAGAACUAAGCUUCCUUCUCUCUUCCAGACCUAGUGAAAGGAGAGUUUCACUCCUUUUUUAUUCUGUUGAUCUUUGUACAUCCAAAGGUUUAUUGUGAAAUAUCUCUCUAUACACUAUAAGUGUCUCUAGGGUAGGUAAAAUGAGUUAUUCAUCCUUUAUACUCAGGUUGAUUUGUUCUCUUUCACUAGCAUGUCUACAUAUUUAACUGUUCCAGUAAAUUUUAAAUUACCAAGUCGUACUUUUUUAAAGAGAGUUUUCAGUUGUCCCCAUAAAACCAUCUGUAGGAGGUUACCUCAAAAUUAACCCUUAGACUCCCAGGGUAUUUGAGAUGGUCAGCCCCCACUUAGAAUCCCAUGGUGUUUGAGAUGGUCGGCCCCCUCUUUGCCCUGUCCUGGCGUUUUAUGGUGGAGAGCUCUAACUCGGCUAACUCUGAGAGAGCCGAAGGAAAGUGCCUUGUCCUUUGUUUCAGAGAGCAGAAGGCCAGAAAUAAACCCCGUGUUUUCUUCCUUCAGGCUGUUCUUUCUCCAUUAACUAAACAGGUCAUCACAUCAGAAGUUGUUUGAAUAAAAUAUCAGACUGCGUUUUAAGGGAAAAAAAAUGUUUUUUAACACUACCAGCAAAGGCCAUCUUUUUGCUUGGCAAAUACAGCCCUCACACACAUGAGCUCUUAGAAAAAAUCUGUUUAGAGGACAGUAAGCUGACUUGAGGUACUGAGAGCAUGGCUUCUCUGUGCCCUGAAAAGUAAUUGAGGACUUCAAGGGAGAUUAACCUUAGUAGAAUCAAUACAUUUUCCUUCCUUCGCUUCUGCCUGCUCCCUAAUGAUUAAGUAUUCACUGCCGCUGCAACUGGGGAUUGCCAGUUUAGUAAAUUUUGAGAUUCUGGUGUGUGUUACACAACAACUUUUUUAAUUUAAAGGAAGGACUUCAUUCCAAGCAUUGUGUGUUUUCUAUGUACCACACAUUGUCCUUAGGUCUGCUGAAAGGCGGGAGUCUUAGUUAACCCUGCUUUUCCUCUGUGACAUUGGGUAAGUCACUUCGCCCUUAUGAACUGUGGUUUUUUUCUCUGUAAACUGAGGGUCUUGGGCUUGACCAUCUUUAUGUUUUCUUUUAGUUGUAUUAUUAUUCAUUUAAAUUGAAUGUGAAUUUAUAUUUAUCUUUCAGAUUCCAAGUCAAUUGUGGUAGUUGCUGGGGAUUUAAAGAUGAGUUGAGGCCAGACAUGGUGGCUCACACCUGUAAUCCCAGUACUUUGGGAGACUGAGUGGGGAGGAUCACCUGAGGUCAGGAGUUGAGACCAGCCUGGCCAACAUAGUGAAACCUCAUCUCUACUAAAAAUACAAAAAUUAGCUGGUCAUGUUGAUGCCUGUUGUAAUCCCAGCUACUCGGGAGGCUGAGGCAGGAGAAUCUCUUGAACCCGGGAGGUGGAGGUUGUAGUGAGCUGAGAUCAUGCCACUGCACUCCAGCCUGGGCAACAGAGUGAGACUCUGUUUCAAACAACAAAGAUGAGUUGAGUGUAGCCCCUAUCCUUCAGAAUCUUCCAGCCAACUUGGGAGAGACUUAAUAGCUAUAGUAGAGGGAUGUGAAAGAUGCUAUGAGAUCUCAGAGGAGGAGAAUUCUAACUCAUCCUCAUGCUUCAGAAAGAGGCUAUUGUCCUGAGACUGAAAGCUCCAAAAUGGAUGGGAGAACUCAAUAAGUUAGGGCUUACUAUAGAAAGGACUGUGCUAGACUCAAGUGUAAUGUGUUGAAUGACUCCAGGUAAUCUAGUGUGCCUCUUCCUGCUUUUCCACUUCAAAGUAAAUUGUUAGAUACAGCAGAGAUGGGCUCUAGAAAGAAGUGGAAGGCCACAUGAUGGCAUGUAUGUAGUUCUGAGGAGGUCGACAUUUGUCUGAUAGAAACAGGAAACAAUUGAACUUGUGACCUUCCUCUUUGGUUGGCCUUUAGAAUAUCAAGUCUGCUCUCCCAACUGUAAGCAGGAGCACAGCCUUGGAGUGACUCCUUAGUGCCACUGAUACCUGGGAAGACUGUUGAUUAUUCAGUGUUUCAGUCCCACCUUUGUCUUGCUUUAACAGGAGCACUAAUUUCCUUUCCUUUUCUCCUUUCCCUUGUCACAAUGAUUCUUUUCAUUUGGUCUACUCCUGUCAUUUUUUUUACCUACCACAAAGUUAGUAGUCCACCAACAUAUCCUUUCCCUUCUCAGAAUGGAGUCCCGCCUGCCAUUUUAUCUUGAGGACCUUAAAAAAUUAAUAACUCUGGUUGUCUAACCUAGGGACUGGAAGAUGACAAAAAUUGUACUACAAAGAAUUGGUAAGGAGUUAUUGUAGCCUAGGUAAGAAAAAAAAUAAGGGUCUUACUAAGACUGGCAGUGGAAAUGGAAAAGAGGUAACACAUUGGAGGGAAAUUUAGGAGGCAGAAUUGACAGGAUCUGAAAUGGUUUGAAUAUUGUUGAGGUAGAGAAGGAGGAUUAGACAAUCCAGACAACUGAAUGGAAGACGGAUAAAAAAAUAAGGGAGAGAAAAGAUAAUUGGUGGGCUUGCAUCUCUGAAGAUAGAAGAAGGGAUUUGAUCUAGAAUGCACAGGAAGAGAUUAGCCUUAAACAGAAAGAAAUUUUUUUUUCUCUGUGGUCUGAAGAGAAGGUCUGGUUGGGAAGAGCAGCCAGUCCACUUGCUUUUAAUAUGCCAUGGGUCAUGCCUUGCUAAAGGAUGUGGUGAUGGAGCUUGAAGGCAGCAACCUUUGCUUCUGUUUGUUUGUCCCACCUUUACUCCGGGGCUUGAGCCUCCUUUUCCAGCCCUCUUCCUCAGAAUGGAGACCAGUGACCUUGAACAGAAAGCUUGGGAGACAGCACCCAUCCUUACCUUCAUCUUUACCCUCAUCCUUCCCCACUGGUGACAAGUUGGGAACCAGUUACAUUCAAGGAUGCCUCUGUGGCCUUCACCGAGGAGGAGUGAGGUCACCUGGACUCUGCUCCCAGGAAGCUGUGCGGAGCUGUGAUGCUGGGCAACUACAGAAACUUGGUCUUGGAGACUUGAAUGAAAAUUCUGUGGAGAAUCUUCAGCAGAAAACACUUCAGGAUCUGUUACAUGAGCUUUCCUCCUGGCUAGUUUUGGAAGGCAUGGCCAGUACAAUUACUGGAAGUCAGGAUUGUAUUGUGAAUCAUCGAGGGGAAGUGGAUGGGGAGCCUGAACUAGAUAUUUCCCCUUGUCAACAGUGGGGAGAAGCAUCUUCUCCUAUUUCCAGAAACAGGGACAGUGUGAUGACUCUUCAAAGUGGUUGUUUCGAAAACAUUGAAAGUGAAACAUAUUUGCCUUUGAAAGUCUCAAGCCAAAUAGACACACAAGACUCUUCAGUGAAGUUCUGUAAGAAUGAGCCUCAGGAUCAUCAGGAAAGCAGACGUCUCUUUGUAAUGGAAGAAAGCACUGAGAGAAAAGUGAUAAAGGGGGAAAGUUGUUCAGAGAACCUUCAAGUUAAACUGGUGUCUGAUGGACAAGAACUGGCCUCGCCAUUGUUAAAUGGUGAGGCAACUUGCCAGAAUGGCCAGUUAAAAGAAUCUUUGGAUCCCAUUGACUGUAACUGCAAAGACAUUCAUGGAUGGAAAUCACAGGUGGUCAGUUGUAGUCAGCAGAGAGCUCAUACAGAGGAGAAACCCUGUGACCAUAAUAACUGUGGGAAAAUACUUAACACCAGCCCAGAUGGUCAUCCAUAUGAGAAAAUCCACACUGCAGAGAAACAAUACGAAUGUAGUCAGUGUGGUAAGAACUUCAGUCAAAGCUCAGAGCUACUACUUCAUCAGAGAGACCACACAGAAGAAAAACCCUACAAAUGUGAGCAAUGUGGGAAGGGCUUCACAAGGAGCUCGAGUCUGCUUAUCCAUCAGGCAGUCCACACAGAUGAGAAGCCUUAUAAGUGUGACAAGUGUGGGAAGGGCUUCACCAGGAGCUCAAGUCUGCUCAUCCAUCAUGCCGUCCAUACAGGCGAAAAACCUUAUAAAUGUGACAAGUGUGGGAAGGGCUUUAGUCAGAGCUCCAAACUGCACAUCCACCAGCGAGUCCACACUGGAGAGAAGCCCUAUGAGUGUGAGGAGUGUGGUAUGAGCUUCAGUCAGCGCUCAAACCUGCACAUCCACCAGCGAGUACACACAGGAGAGAGGCCCUACAAGUGUGGUGAGUGUGGGAAGGGCUUCAGUCAGAGCUCGAACCUUCACAUUCACCGGUGCAUCCACACAGGAGAGAAGCCUUACCAAUGCUAUGAGUGUGGGAAGGGUUUCAGCCAGAGCUCGGAUCUUCGCAUCCAUCUCAGAGUCCACACUGGAGAGAAGCCCUAUCACUGUGGCAAGUGUGGGAAGGGAUUUAGCCAGAGUUCCAAACUCCUCAUCCACCAGAGAGUACAUACUGGAGAGAAGCCCUAUGAGUGCAGCAAGUGUGGGAAGGGCUUCAGCCAGAGCUCCAACCUUCACAUCCACCAGCGGGUUCACAAGAAAGAUCCUCGCUAACUGACAUUAGCCCAUUCAGGUCUUCACAGCGCUCAUACUGUAAAAACUGUUAAAUAUUUAGUAUCACUCUUACUUUAUAUUCUACAAAGGAGAGAGAUGUAAGGGUUAUUUAGAUAUGUUCCCUCACUGAAAAAUCACUCAUUCAAAAUAUUUAAGUAUCAAGCACUUUGUUAUGCUGUACAAUGAAUGGAUUGUUCUUGUUUCUCAGAUGGGUAGAGUAAAAGUGUCUGUACUUUACAAUUCAACUACAUGUUCUACCCAGCAUUUUAACGGCAAGAACUUUAUAUUUAUUCUCAAGCAGGGCAUGUUUCCCUUUGUUCACAUUCUCUGAGAAAUUGAAACUCUGGUUUCUCUUCAAA